AUUAAUGAGACAAAAUGUGGGAACAGCAUUUGAAACUUUAUAUCAGCAUCCACCCAUCCACCCACCCACCUAUCCAUCCAUCUAGCCACCUGUACACCCACCCAGCCACCCACUCGUUCAUCUGUCCUUCCAUCCGUGCACCUACCCACCCGUUCCUCUAUCCAUUCACCCACCCAUCCAUCAUCCAUCCAUCCACUCAUUCAUCUGUCCAUCCAUCCAUGCACCUACCCACCCAUUCCUCUAUCCAUCCACCCACCCAUCCAUCCACCAUCCAGCCACCCACGCACCCGCACAUUCAUCCAUCGAUUUACCCAUCCAUCCGUCUACCCAUCCAUCUAUCAUCUCCCCAGCCACCACCUACCCAUCCACCCAUCCACCCACCCAGCGACCCACCCAUGCACCCGCACAUCCAUCCAUCAAUUUACCCAUCCAUCCGUCUACCCAUCCAUCUAUCAUCUCCCCAGCUACCACCUACCCAUCCACCCAUCCAUCUAUCCACCAUGUACUCACUCACCCACCCACACAUCCACCCGCCCACCCACUCAUUCAUCUCUCCAUCCAUCCAUGCACCUAUGCACCCAUUUCUCUAUCCAUCCACCCACCCACCCAUCCAUCCAUUCAUCCAUCCAUCCACCCACCCACCCACCCACUCAUGCACCCACACAUCCAUCUAUCCAUUUACCCAUCCAUCCAUAUACCCAUCCACCCAUUCCUCCAUCCAUCCAUCAUCUCCCCAACCACCAUCUACCCAUCCAUCCAUUCAUCUAUCCACCAUGAACUCACCCACCCACCCACCCACCCAUUCUUUCCUCUAUCCAUCCAUUCAUCCACUCACCAAUCCACCAUCCAUUCAUCCAUCCAUCCACCUACCCAUCCAUUAAUCCAUCUACCUCCUGUCCACUCACCCACUCAUUCUUCUAUCCAUCCAUCUACCCACCCAUCCAUCUAUUCAUCCAUUCAUGCACCCAUUCAUCCACCCAUCCAACCCACGAAUCCACCUACCCACCCAUCCAUUCAUCCACCCAUCUGUCCUAACAUCCACCCACUGAUCUACUCAUUCAUCUGCACAUCCAUUCAUCCUGCCCAUCCUCCACCAUCAACCUUCCUAUUGAUCUGUCAGUUAUUAAAGUUAAUUGCCAAACAUAAAUAUAAAAUGUUAGGGUAAAGGCCCCAAGUUUUCUCUGUUACCUACCUACGUCUCUCUUUUUGUUAUUAUAAUUACGAAUGAAUCCUUGAAAUCUUUAAACAUCUUUAUUGACCCAUGUGGGUUGUAUUGUGGUUAAUAUUGUAGUCAUUUACGUUUACACCUGCAAGUGUUGCCAUCAAAAGCUUAGGCCUCUCCUUCCCUCUUCCCCCAAGACACACCCUGUCACAGCACAUCCAUAUCCACACACACAGCAGGUCUUACUUCUGAAUGUUCUGUGUGGAAUUUGAGCUUUUGGCAGAGCUUGUGGAUUGACCUCAUGGUUGAGAUUUGCUGUCUUCAUGGACAGGUGGGAGUGUUCAUUUUAAAGUUAAAUUUAAUAAAUAUUUAGAAAGCAUGCAUCAUAUGCCUCAUUAGCAAUUUUGUUAGGUACUCUGGGAGAAACAAACAAGCAAGAGCGCAGAAUCAUCUGGUCCGUCUGUGGCCCCUGCAAUUCCGUGAGGCACUGCUUCCUCUGCACAUGAGGUUCCUGGGGAGCAUGUCAUCUGCCUUAUUAUGGUCGACUGCACCCUCUGUUUGGUGGGGGGCAUGGGUUCCCCUAAGUGGGAGCUGUGCCUGAGUCAGCGUCAUGAGGGAAAAUGUGGAGAAACCUCAGGGGCAACCAUUCCAUGUGGAGCUCGUGGGCAGGAGUCAUCCUGAGUCUGCAGGACCCAUGUGUACCUGGGCUGUACGGAUGCAUGUGUGACUUCAUCCCAGCCCCUCUAUUCUUGAGAGCUUAUUCAGUAUCAGAAAUAAUGGGGAGACGAGGUGAGACAGGCACGUGAGGGCAGCCGUGUGUAGUCUUGUGUUGGAUUCAGGUGAUAUCAAUUUUGGAGGCCUGCCUGAAGUUUUUGCUGAGUUUAUUCCAGCAGGAAAUACUACCACACCUAAUUAAUCUUCAUACAGGACUUUGCCAAUUGCUAUGAUAUGGGGCAUUGGCAUUAUUAGCAUCAUCACUUUUCAUAUGUGAAACCGAGGAUCGGGUAGAUUAAGUGCUGUGCCCAGGUCAGCCCAAGUCAGAAGGCUCAGGGCUGGCUCUCAGGGCCACAUCUUUGAUCCUGGCUCUCUGUCCGUCUCACUAUGGCCCAUGUAUCCCUAAGACAUGUGGAAAGCAGGGUUUCUCCAGUGGAGGGAACCAGAGCAGACAGCAUGAUCAUUUCUGCUUCAAGGGGGCAGAGGCAAUUGGAGUUUCUCACAUCACCCAGCUCAGAAUGGCAGCUGGUGGCCUGCAGGUGAGGGGCAGGGCCCUUGCAGCUCUGCCACCUGGUGUGCAUGCUGGCUGUUCUCCAGCCUCUCUUCCUCUUGAUUUUCUUGUCUCGGGUUGUUGACUUUUGCUUUUGGCCUGGUGGAGACUAAGGGGAACAGUGUGCAAAGUGCUGAGCCCGUGUCUUGCACAGAGCAUCACUCGGGGCUCAGAGCACUGCAGCUAUUAUUACUCCUUUCUAAAAAGCCAGUAUCUGCCUGGAAUUACAAGGCAGGCACUGACAGAUGUAUAAGUAGAUGCUCAAGAGCAAAUUAAAAAUGCAUUGUUAAAAAUGGAUUCAAUGUGUGAACAAAGAUUGGCAUGAAGGUUGGGUCCCUGUAUUUUUAGAGGCUAAUUAAAGUGUGCGAACAACGAUAAAUUCAGAUAACCCGUAUUGCUUGAAGUCACCACAAAGCAUUCACUGAAGAGCUAAUUGCAGCCUCCAGAGGUUUGGGUGGUCUGCGGCCAUCACUGACUUCAGGCUCUGCCUGCUUUUGCCCAUGCUGAGACUGCACUGUGCCCUUGGGGUCCCUGUGCAGCCCUGGGGAUCUCGCUGCCCUGGCGCCUGGUGAUGUGCAUUCUGGUGCAUUUCUGCAGUCCUGAGUUUGGGAUAGACAGUAACACCGUCGUGUUACCACGUGCCACUUGUCUAAAUCACUCACAGAAAUCUGUGGUCAGGUUUCUAUAAAGUGCUUGAUUGGUGAUGAGGAGAUGGGGAGUGAUUUAUGGCAUGCUGGCCCUCCAGCUAUUGAUGGGUGUACACACACCGAGGUCAGUGCCAUAUAAAAUGCAGAUACCACAGCCCCUAAGGGGUGGCUGGCCAGCUGUCAUGGCUGCAGUCGGUAUUGGAGUGGGCAGGAGUCUGUAAGGAAAUGUGAUCCAUGGGCUUAGAAUCCCCUGUUUUGUCAGUGUCUUGGAAAAUUGGCCUCCAGAGAUCAACUGUGGAGUGCGCCAUGUCAGAGGCUGUCUUCUCCUGUUGCGACAUUUAGCAGACCAGGUCUGCACACCUGAUUUUCCAUUAGUCACACUAGAAAGGAGAACAUUUGUGCUUCAUAACCUCAGGGUUAGACAAACAGCCCUGCAGGUAGAUCAUGAUCAAUAACAGGAGAUCUUUGUAAACUAGGUUAAUUUUGUUCCUGAAAAUCUGCAAUGUUUUUUUAUCUACAAGGGUUUUUUUUUUUUUUUAAAUUUCCUAAUAGAACAUGAGUAUUCACUGCACACAGACACAGUGAUGGUGGGCUAAGGACAAAAAAGACCUUGGGUAAACUCUAGACCUCUACCUGUCAUGAUUAGAAACAUAUCCGUUCUCACCAGAUAAUCUUUUAAAUUCCAACCAGGCUUGCUUUAGGUGCCAGGAGGUAGUAAGAAUUACAGGUUCUGUUUUUAGGGCAACGGCAGGAUUUUAAACUCUGUAUGCCUCCCCUUUCUGUCACUAAGCCACCACUUUUUUACAAAAAGCUUUGUUUUGAAAUAAUUGUAGAUUUUCAGAAGACUUACGAAGAUUGUGCAGAGUUCCUAUAUGCCCUGCUUCCUGUAAAGGCAUUAACAUCAUAUGUAAUCAUGGCACGCGUAUCACAACUAAGAAAUUAACGUUGGUAGAAAACUGCUAACGAAAACCAUAGACUUGACUUGAAUUUCACUAGUUGUUCUACCAACUAAUGUCCUUCUUCUGUUCCCAGGUGCAGUCCAGGAUGCCAUGUUGCAUCUAACCACUGCUUUUUAUUCUUUGUUCUUUAAAUAAUUUUAUUUUUAACUUUUUAUUACGGUAAAAAUUUCAAACUCUGUAGUAGAGAGCAUGCUAGUAGGUCCAGUUGACGGCCGCCCAUUUUCAGCCAUGUUCCGCUUGUCGUGUGAAUGAAGGUGGUCUUAGUGAGGGGCCCAGCCCUGGCAGCACCCUCCACGCACGCACAGGGUCUGCAAAGUUUGUGCCUGGCGGUGUGCUUGUCUUGCAUCUCUAGUCACCGUGUUCUUGCUGAUGGCGCUCCAGGGUUGCUACUGUAAGCGCCUGUGCUUAAGAACUGGAUCUGAGCUUUCCCCGAUUUCUGCCACAGUUUUCAUAGGCCACGGGAUUUGCUGGAGAACCCGCUCACUCUGGAGCCUUUAGUCAUGAUGUCCAGUUGAGAUUUAUUGUUCAGUGUGACCCAGUGGUUCAGAAAACCUGUCCAACUGCACACAGCGCCGCCCCCCGCCUUUUUUUUUUUUUUUUUAAAGACAGAGUCUCCCUCUCUUGCCCAGGCUGGAGUACAAUGGCACGAUCUUGGCUCACUGCAACCUCCACCUCCCAGGAUCAAGCGAUUCUACUGCCUCAGCCUCCUGAGUAGCUGGGAUUACAGGCGUGUGCCACCAUGCCUGGCUAAUUUUGGUAUUUUUUUAGUACAUACACUGUUUCUCCAUGUUGGUCAGGCUGUUCUCAAACUCCUGACCUCGUGAUCCGCCUGCCUCGGCCUCCCAAAGUGCUGGGACUACAGGCGCGAGCCACCGCGCCCGGCCAUAGCCCCACUUUUUUGAGCUGUGAUUGUAAGAGCUGGACUAAAACAAAAUGUCUGACAGAAGAAAAACUACCUUAUUUCCACAUCAUACUUCCCCUCGGUGCCCAGGGUCCAGUGUCACCUCUGGAUGCCCAGUGUCCUCCUUUGCCCUGGCAGAGCUUUCUGUUUCUGUGCCUGUGCAGGUUAUUGGCUGGUGUGGGCACAGCGACCACCCCAUAAGAUGUGAUGUAGCAAUUGUGGAAUGAACCACUGGCCUGCUAGUAGGUUUGUAAGUUUAACUGCUAAGCUACUUUACACCAAGAUGUUAAUAGCUCUUAGUGUUUUUAAGUGUUAACUGCUUGUGGUUAUUUACAUUUUUGAAGUAUUUUAUUUUAAAAAUGGACACAUAAUAAUUACAUAUUUAUGGGGUACAUAGUGAUGUUUUGAUACAUAUGUGUCGUGAUCAGAUCAGGGUAAUUAGCAUCUCCAUCAUCUCAAACAUUUGUCAUUUCUUUGUGCUGGGAACAUUCAGUAUCCUCCUAGCUAAUUGAAAUUGUAUAUUAUGUUACUGUUACUUAUAAUCAUCAUACAGUGGUAUAGAACACUAGAACUCCUAUCUAGCUGUAAUUUUGCAUACCUUAACAACUCUCUCCCUAUCCCCCUUUCCCUACAACCCUUCCCAACUUCUAGUAUUCCCUUUUCUACUUUUUACUUCUAUGAGGUCAACUUUUUACAGCAUCCACACAUGAGUGAGAACCUGUGGUGUUUAACUUUCUGUUCCUGGCUUAUUUCACCUAACAUAAUGCCCUCUAGUUCCCUCUAUGUUGCUGCAAAUGAUGGCUUUUCAUUUUGUAUGGCUGAUUGGUACGCCAUGGUGUAUAUGUUCCACAUUUUGUCUCUCUGCUCCUCUGUUGUGGAUCACCUAGGUUGAUUCUGUAUCUUGGUUAUUGUGAAUAGUGCUGCAGUAAAUGUGGAGGUGCAGGUGUCUCUUCCAUAUCCUGAUUUCCUUUCCUUUGGGUAAAUGCCGAGUAGCAGGACUGCUGGAUCAUAUGGGAGUUCUAGUUGUAGUUUUCAGAGGAACUUCUAUACUGUUCUGUAGUGACUGUACCAGCUUACAUUCCCACCAACAGUGUGUAACAGUUCCCUUUCUCUGCAUCCACACCAACAUUUAUUUCUUGUCUUUUUGAUAGUGGCCAUGCUAACUGGGGUGAGAUGGUACCUCAUUGUGGUUUUGAUUUGUAUUUCCCUGAUAAUUAGUGAUGUUGCACAUUUUUCAUAUAUUAAUAUUUGUUAAUCAUUUGUAUGUUUCCUUUUGAGAAAUGUCCGCACUCAAAUUUUCUCAUUUUAAAAUUAGAUCUUUUUUUUUUUUGCUGUUGAAAUGUUUGAGUUCCUUGUAUAUUUUGUAUAUUAAUCCUUCAUCAGAUGCAUUGUCUGCAGGUAUGUCCUCUGAUUCUGUAGGUCAUGUUUUUACUCUGUUGAUUGCUUCCCUUGCUGUGCAGAAGCUUUUAGGUCGAUAUAAUCCCAUUUGAUUAUUUUUGCUUUUGUUGCCCAUGCUUUUGGAGUCUUACUUAUAAAUUUUUUCCCUGGACCAAUGUCUUGAAGCAUUUCCCUGUGUUUUCUUCUAAUGGUUUUAGAGUUUAGUGUCUUACAUUUAGGUCUUUGAUGCAUUUUGAGUUGAUUUUUGUAUACGGUGACAGGUAGGGGUCUAGUUUUAUUUUUCUGCAUAUGCAUAUAGUUUUCCCAGCAUUAUUUAUUUAUUUUACGUUCAGGGGUACAUGUGCAGGAAGUGCUGGUUUGUUACAUAGGUAAACGUGCCUAGCACUAUUUAUCGAAGAGAAUGUCCUUAAUGAGUGUUCUUGGCCUCUUUGUCAGAAAUCAGUUGGCUUGUGUAUAUGUGGAUUAAUGUCUGUUCUCUCUAUUCUGUUCCAUUGAUCUAUGUGUCUGUUUUUAUGCCAGUAUCAUGCUGUUUUGGUUAUUAUAGCUUUAUAGUAUAUUUUGAGGUCUGGUAGUGUGAUACCUCCAAUUUUGUUCUUUUUGCUCAGGAUUGCUUUGGCUAUUUUAUAAUUCCAUAUGAAACUUUGGCUUUUUUUUUCCUAUUUCUGUGAAGAAUGUCAUUGGUAUUUUGGUGCUUAAUAGAAGGAAAUAAGUAAAGAUAAGAGCAGAAAUACACAAAAUUGAGACAAAAAACAAAGAUCAAUGAAACAAAAAGUUGGAUUUUGGAAGAAAUAACAGUAUUAACAAACCAUUAACUAGACUAAGAAAAAAAGAGAAAAAUACCCAAAUAAAUAAAAUCAGAAGUGAAAAAGUGAAACAUCACAAUGGAUACCAGAGAAAUAUAAAGGAUCAUUAGAGAAUAUUAUGAAUAACUACAUGCCACUAAAGUAAAAAACCUAGAGGAAAUGGCUGAAUUCCUGGACACAUGCAGCCUACCAAGAUUGAGCCAAGAAGAAAAAGAAAACCUGGGCAGACUAACAAGAAAUGAAGUUGAAUCAGUAAUAAAAGUCUGUCACAGCAGAAAGGCCUAGGACUGGAUGGCUUCAUUGCUGAAUUCUACCAAACCUUUAAAGAAGAAUUCAUACUAGUUCUUCUCAAACUAUUCCAAAUAAAUUGUAUCAGAGAUAAUUCUUCCUGACUUAUUCUACAAGGCCAGCAUAACCCUGACACAAAAAGCAAAUAAGAACACAGCAAAUAAAACCACAGGUCAAUAUUCUUGAUGAAUAUAGAUGCAAAAAUCCUACACAAAAUAAUAGCAAACCAAAUCCAGCAACACAUCAAAAAGCUAGUACAUGAUGAUUGAAUGGGAUUCAUCCCAGGGAUGCAAAGAUGGUUCAGUAUACAUAAAUCAAGAAAUGUGAUUAAAUCACAUCAGCAGAAUGAAGGACAAAAACCACAUGAACAUCUCAAUAGAUGCAGAAAAAGCAUUUGAUAACCUUUAGCACCCAUUCAUGAUAAAAACUCCCAAUAAACUAGGUAUAGAAGGAAUGUACCUCAACACAAUAAGGGCCAUAAAUGACAAAACCACAGCUGACAUCGUACUAAAUGGGGAAAAGCUGAAUACUUUUCCUUUAAGAACUGGAACAAGAAAAGAAUGCCCAUUCUCACCACUCCUAUUCAACACGUACUGGAAGUCAUAGCCAGAGCAGUCAGGCAAGAGAAAGAAAGGACAUCCAAAUUUGAAAGGAGGAAGUCAGAUUAUCCCUGUUUGCAAAUGACAUGAUCUUAUAUAGAGAAAAACCUGAAGACUCUACCAAAAAGCUCUUAGAACUGGUAAAUGAAUUCAGUAAAGUUGCAGGAUACAAAAUCACCAUACAAAAAUCAAUAUUGUUUCUAUAGACAAACAACUAGGUGAAAAAGAAAUCAAGAUGACAAUUCCAUUUGCAGUAGCUACAAAAAAUUUAAAAUACCUAGGGAUAAACUUUACCAAGGAGGCCAAAGACCUCUACAAGGAAAACUACAAAGCAUCGAUGAAAAGAAAUUGAAGAGGACUGACAAACAAAUGGAAAGUACUUGGAAGAAGUACUGUAUGGUUCAGAUGACCAUACUGCCCAAAGAAAUCUACAGCUUCAAUGAAGCCUCUGUUUGCAUUUUAAGGAGAUGAUAUUCUUGAAGAAAAAUUGUUUAUCCCAAAUGCAGAGUUCCUGACUUGUGGCCCAUUAUUGAGGAGGCUAUGGUGCUUUUCUCCUUGGUCUUCAAAACAAGUUAGUCAUGGAUAUGGAAACUCAACCCUCAUGACUAAAAGAAGCAAACUGAAAAGAAUGUCAUUUAUAUGGUUCUGUAGAUAUAUGAUUGUUUGGAGGGGACUUGGGUCCUCCCAGGAGAAACAGUCUGCAUUGGAAUGUCUCCUUGUAUUAGAAUAUAUCUCUUGCCAGCUUCAUUGGUUUUUGUUUGUUUGUUUGUUUUUUUGAGAUGGAGUUUUGCUCUUGUUGCCCAGGCUGGAGUGCAAUGGUGCAAUCUCGGCUCACUGCAACCUCCACCUCCUGGGUUCAAGCAAUUCUCCUGCCUCAGCCUCUGGAUGGAGUAGCUGGGAUUACAGGCGCCCAUCACCACACCCAGCUAAUUUUUGUAUUUUUAGUAGAGAUGGGGUUUCAUCAUGUUGGUCAGGCUGGUCUCGAACUCCUGAGCUCAGGUGAUCCACCCACCUCGUCCUCCCAAAGUGCUGGGAUUACAGGCGUGAGCAACUGUGCCCGGCCUUCCACAGUUAUUCACUGUGCACACUUGGCCAGGUGUACCGCUAGGUGCGGGGACCCAGGGUGGGCCACAGCCCCAUGUCUGACCAGAUGACUGACCUCAGGCAGCCUUUGAUGCACAAAUGAUGAACUUCCAAUUGCUUAAUGUUAUUACAAUUACAGACUGAUGACGAGGUUGGUGCUGCAGCUGCACCCUGGGAACUCGGUGGUGCCCCCCACCAUACUGGGCACGGUGGGACUGCCGCAGAUGUGAUGGAUGACAAGGGUUCCUGCCAGUGAGAGGAAUGAAGAUGCUCUUUGCUUCUGUGAGGUCAAGGCCUCAUUUCAUGUGACAUGCAGAACCAGCCUCACUUGCCGUCGGCCCUCCACAUCCACAGCUGUUUCUGCGCAGGGAUGUCUGGCUCUGAGCCCUUCUGCGGAGCAGUGUUGCGCUGUUCCUAGAAUAGUGUCCUUGUAGUCUCGUUAGGCUUUGCUUCUCUUUGUGUCUUGUUGUUUUGCUGGUUUUCCAGACCACUAGCUGUACCACGAGGCUUCUGUGAGCAGAUGGCAUGAGACAGGUGAGUGCUUGCAUGGAAACCGGGGCACUGGGGGUCCAGGGUGCAGGCCUGCUUCACUCUGGGCACCCUGUAACUGCUCCUGCUCCCAAGUGCCAGUGAUAUUCUGCAGAUACAAAUGUGUGAUCACAUUGCCUGGGCCCCAGUCUCCGAGGAGCCUGGUGGUGGUGGUGGUGGGCAUUUUCAGCCUGGGUGUGCUGUCAGGACCCGAGAAGGUGACAGGAGAAGGUGGGAGGUGAGGAGGAGUGUCAGACGUGGGGUGGGGGGUGUGAGGCUGGAGACCAGGACCCUCGCCCGGAGCCUUGCUGUGAUCGGCUGUGGUGGGGAAGCUGGGCGCCACUGCUCUCAGCAUGAAUGUGCUCAGGCUGUUGACUGAAGGGUGUUGCUCACUCUUUUUUAAGAAGCAUGAUAUACAUCUAGGAAGAGUAAUAUUUUAAAAGUCUUUUUCCCUUUUCCACACCUCCGCUUGAAGGAACUCCAAAGCCUGCAGGGUAAAUGAGCAGUGUUAGGAUGGCCAAGAGCUCUCAGGCUGAUUUAGUACUUGUGGGCAGGGCCCCUUUUCGGAUUGAUUAUGACACAUGGUGCUAAUGGGGUUGAUUUCUAGUGGGAGGUACAGUAUGUGUUACCCUUCGAGUUCUGCAAAUGAAGUGGGGGGAGGAAGGAAUGCAUUCAAAGAAAAGAGAGUGGAAUUCGGAAUAAUUUUUUUUGAUAUUCUCUUAAAGGCACAAUGAUCAGAACCUGCCAUGUUUUAUUUCUUUUCAUUAGAAUUAAGCUUAGGUUCUGGGUAUCGGAGCAUCUCUGGCACAGGUUGUAUUCACCCUUUGGCCCUCAGAUGUCACUGAACAGGAAGCUGCCGGGUGAGUUUUUGAUAACAAAUCUCAUGGCAGGAUGGUGGCGCCUCCCUCGCCUGCUCACCUGCCCUCCAGGCUGGUACUCACUGAGUGCCCAGUGUGUGCCCAGCCCUAGAGCCGAGGCCGCAGAAGGCCCUGUGCUUGGGGGCUUGCUGCGAUACGGGGCAUCCCAGGAAUCCAGGACUCAGAUGAGUCAAUGCAGACCUGCUGCUGGGAGAUAGUGCUGGAGGGGAGGAGAGUGCUGGCAGAGAAGCAUAAGCCCCGGCGAGAUUCCACUGAGGGGAAGCCCAGGGAUUUCUGGAGGCAGGUGAUGGAGCUGAGGGCUGAACACGGACGGGCGGUGUCGCGCCGUGAAGGCAGAAGAGCCUGUCUGGGUGGAGGGCACAGCCCGAGGCCCAGGGGAGGCAGGGAGCUUUUCGGGUCCAGAGCUGAUGGGGUGAGGAGUGAGGGGCCCCAGGUGGACUCAGGGUUUUCUUUUCUGAGGCUGAGUGGGAUCUUAUAGGCCUUGGGGAGCCAUUGGAGUGUUUUCAGCAGCAGUGACAGGGUCUGUUUGCACUGGGCCACGGUCUGGAGACUGGGCAGUUUGGGGGUUGGAGGAGUUUCCCUGGCCCAGCUGAGCAGGGCUGGCGCGGACAGAGAGAAUCCCGCCUCUUCAAGGUCGCUCAGCUGACCAUGGGCAUAGCUGGACCUAGAGUGCCAGCGACCCUCCAUGCUUCUGCCAGGAAGUCCAGCGGCAUCUUUCCAUUCAUGGUGGUUACGGAAUUGGCCGAGUCCUUACUCUGACCUACAGUGAGCCUCAAGAAACAAAAAUGUCCACCUGUGUUCAACAAAUUAAACAUGUAAAAGAACAUACUGGGCGUGGUGGCCCACACCUGUCAUCCCAGAGCUUUGGGAGGCUGAGGCAGGAGGAUCAUUUGAGCCCAAGAGUUUGAGACUAGACUGGGAAACGUAGGGAAACUGUUGUCUUUACAAAAGCCCCCAAAAUUAGCUGGGCGUAGUGGCACUUGCCUGUGGUCCCAGCAACUUAGGAGCGUGAGGCAUGAGAAUCGCUUGAGCCCAGGAGGCAGAGGUGGCAGUGAGCUGAGAUGGUUCCACUACACCCCAGCCUGGGCAACAGAACGGGACCCUGUCUCAAAAAAAGUUAAAUAAAAGAAAAACCCAAUUCUUCUUGUUUAAUAGGGCAGCAAGACUAAAACAGUAAUCAUCAGAUGAAAUGAUAGUAGAAAAUAUGAAAUAUGAACAAAUGAUUGAACCCGUGAGGGCUCGAGACUAAGGGGCAGAGACACAGCCAGGGUGUCUGGGUUCAGCAGAUACUUCCAGAGCCCUGCUGUGUGCUGGGCACAGGGGCUGCAGACAGAUGCCCGCCCCCCCCAGCCCCGGGAUGCUCCACACCCAGCAGGUGCUGUUGGAUACACAGUGGGAGCUCCUCCUGGCCUAGGGUCUGUGCUGGGAGAGGCAGAGGCAGACAAUGGAAAGGCUCCACUCUCAACAAAGAGUGGGGUUUGAUGUACUGGGGUCCGAGAAGGUAGCAUUAGAGCAGGGAGUGACCAUAUGGGUACUGGGGAAGAUUCUAGGCUGAGGCAACUCUGUGCAAAGGCUGUGGGUGAGCGGUUGCCUGGAGUGGUCAAGGCCACAUGGCUGGAGAGGAGCAGGGGGUGCAGAGGGCACAUGUGCAUGCAUGUGCACAUACAGGCAUGUGUGAACAUAUGUGUGGGUAUGUGUGAUUUCCCAUAGGGCCCAGGGUCCAGGUGGGAUGGGAGCCCUUCCAGGUUUGGAGCAGAGCAGUGUCUGGGUGUAGGUUUCCAGAGGGUCAGGGUCUCUGGGGAAUAGAUCACGGUGGAGGCCCAAGGGAGAGGCAGGGUGCCAUAGGGGCUGUUGCAGCGUUGAGGCCCUAGGGACGGCUCCCCAGGCCAGGGCUGUGGGGUGCUUGGAGUGGAGGAGGAACCAGAGGAUGCACUGAGGUGGAGAGCUGGCCGAGGGAGAUGUGGUGCGUCUGAAUUUCUGCUGAGCACUGGAAUUCCAUUUUAUCAGGAUGAGGAUGGCUGGGGAAGGGAUGGCUUUGAUCAUUGCUUUUAUUGUGAGGAGACAAUUUGUCAUCAGCAUUGGUGUUAUUUUGGCCUGACUUUUAUCACUCUUGUUCAUCAUGAUCUUGUUUCUGCCUAACUUUCGUGCUUGCUACCCUCUUAGAAAAUGAUGUAUCACUUAUUUAGGAUAUUAUGUGUUAAUUGUUGUCCAGAAAUCAAACUAAGUUUCUUUCCAAGAAAGACGUGAUGUAAAGCACUUUGAUUCCCUGGGAGAACAGGUGCUGUGUGUGCACAAGGUUUUGCUGCCUGAUUAUUCUAGGGAAAAUGAGACAGUGAUUAUAUAUGUUGGCAGGACUCAGAUCACAAACUGCCCUGGAUGUAGGGGGAGGCUUGGGUGAAUCUAAAAGCAUCCUCCUGCCAUUUGAGGUGAGUCCUCUCCAUGUUGGGAGUAGAAAUGGCUCUUCUUUUAAAAUAGGGUCCCUUUCUUGGCUCUGUCUCUGAGUCACCCUCCUGGGGUCACAGAUCAGCUGCAUGGGCACAGGUUAGGAAUGUGGUCUCAGCCUCAGCCUUGGACCCCAUCCCCCCAUCAAAAUCUGCCUUUUAACAAGAUCCAAGGGGAUUCUUGUGCACCUUAAAGUUUGGGAAAUACUGAGUUAGGACAGUUUUAAAACAUUCUGAGGACUUCUUGCUUCGAGAUCAGUAUUGUAUUAGGGCAGCUGGGUUUAAAUCCCAGGAAUGCCAGCAGGUGUGUAGGACUGGUGUGAACAGUGCUGAGUACUUGGGUCAGGUUACAGAUCGACCCCACUAGCAUCCAGCAAUCUGGCACCCCAUGGAUGUUUCCAUAGAGAGCCCUUUGAAAACGAGAGCCCUGGUAAGCUGGUGUGUGUGCUGGCAUGGAAGAGAGAGCCUCUCUUUCCUAAGGAAGGCGUCAAAAGCAGGGGUUAGGUGAAUGGAGGGAGCCCAGGCACGUCAGUGCCCAGUGUGGCAGGUGUGUGUGCCGGGGAAGGAAACCUGUGUUGUUGGAACGAAGUUGCCAUUUGGCGGAAUUUGGUGCACUUACUUGGAAAAUAUUGCCCAAAGAACUCAGAACUGUCUGUUUUCUUUUCCUUAAACAUUUCUCUUGUCAGAGUGAUGAGAAAAUUGCCUAUGUGGGAACUUGAGAAGUGCAAAUUUGUUAAUACUUCCUUUGACAAUGGUUUGUAUUCAGAGCUGUUUAUGAGCUGUCACAAAUCAUUUCCAGUUAAAACGUUUCUGCCAUGGAGUCAUGCCGCGCUGGAGGGUCCGGCGGGACAGACGUGCACAGCCUCGCGGCCCUGGCUCAGAAAGGCCUGAACCCAUGUGCCGUGGGUCUGGUUUUUAAGCUGGUGAAUUGAAUCGUGGAGAAUAAAAAUGACCUGGUUUCUGUGGAAACCUCUGCUUUGAAAAUGUUCUUCCUUUUAAUGAUCUUCAGAAGCCCAGUGUCAAGGCCUGAGUGUGAGAUUUCGCCAUUCUUUUGAUGGCUGGGACAGAGCAGAAUUCAGUGCCAGUCCUUUCGUUCUGUAAUGAUGAUGUUUGUGAGACUUGGGGAUGACACUUUUGGCUCAUCCCUGGUAGGACGUGGACAUGCGGUUGCUUUUCCAUGAGCAGGGAUGGGUUUCCCUGACCCACUGCCCUGCCCCAUCCAUGCUGUGCUCAUGGGCAGGCGUGUGUGGGGUGGCAGCCUGGGCUUCAGAGUCCGGCCUGCAGCCUGGAUGUGAGACACUGAGUGAUCAUAUAGGGGAUGAUUUUAUAGGUCUGGAUGCUUUAUAGCAGUGGCUCUCACCUGGGGGUGACUUUGUUCCCCAGAGGCCAUUUGACAAUGUCUGGAGACAUUUUUGGUUGUCACAAGUGGGAGGUGGGAGGUGCUCCUAGCAUCUAGUGGGGAGAGACCAGGGAUGCUGUUAGACUGCCCACAGUCCACGGGACAGCCUCAUCACAAGGGUUUGUCCAACCCAAUGUGUCUGUCGUGCCCAGGUUGAGAAACCUGCUUUAACAGUAGUGGUAGUUUGGAUAGAUGGAUAAUGGUAAAGAUGAGAAAAGGAUACAAUGGGGCUGGGUGCAGUGGCUUAGGCCUGUAAUGCCAGGCUGAGGCAGAAGGAUCGCUUGAGCCGAGGAAUUGGAGGCUGUGAUCAUACCACUGCACUUCAGCCUGGGCAACAGAGCAAAACCCUAUCUUAAAAGAAAGAAAGAAAGAAAAAAGCAUACAAUGGCCAGAUAGUGGUUGAAAACAUGUUAGAUCUCCAAUAUCUGGUUCCAUUUCUUUUUGUUUUUCAUUUAUUUACUUAGUAUUCAGAAAAGAAAUUUCACUGUCCAAAAUCCAUUUUUUCCCAACCAAGACAGUUGAAAAUUCCUAAAUUCUAAAUAAUCAGACACCUUCAGUAGGUACGCUUACUUUUCUUCCAUGCUUCCGUAGUAUUUUGCUUAACAGAGAAUGUUAGGGUUUUCUUUUUGAAGCUCCUAGUUUGUCUUAAUGAGUUAAUUCUACGAAAUCCUUUUUUUUUUUCUUUUGUUAGCAUUAACAUGGAAUCUGCUAAUGAAUGGCCACUAGGGACGAUGGUGAAAACACUUGAAAUGAGAUGCCUCUAUUUGAAUAUUUUAUGGUCAUGGAAUUGGCUAUUUAUUUUAUUUUUGCUUUUAUGAUUUCAAAAUUCAGAUUUCUUUGAGCAAAUGUUUAGAGAUGACAAGAGGGAAACUCAGGGAUGGAAUAAUCUAUUGAGUGUGAACCAAAGAUUACAUUCUUUUUCAGAAUUGUCCUUCCUUCCUUUUUACUGGGUCCCAUAAAAGGUUUUAUGAUCUGAUUGUACCUUAUUGAUAUUUGCCAAUUGAUAAAUUUCUUGUUCAUUAAUUCAGUAUUUAGGUCAAUGAUGUUUCUUCCUGGCUUAGUAUGAAGUUUAGCCUUUCAUGAUACAUAUUUCCUCUUUCUUUAGCUAGAUUACCAAUAAUGUUCAAAUGGGGCAGGGGAAGGAUUACACCAGAAAAACUAGCCUUUUACCUCUGUGAAAAGGUGCCUCCCAGAAGCACCAUCUAAAAGCAGGUCAUGAUUUUAAUCCAGAAUGGCCAAGUGCUGCUGCUGUGUACAACUUCCGACCAGCAUGAUGCUGGACAGCAGGUCUCUAGGUGGGUUCAUUGAGUAUUUAGGUCAAUGAUCUUGUUGUGCUCCAUUCGGGAUGACUGAGUAUUCCUGAAACAAAUGCUAUUUCUGGCUGCUGCCAUUCCCGCAGAGCACUUGUGCAAGUUCAUAAGACUUCCUAAGUGAAAGGGGAAUUUGCAUAGUUUGUGGAUUCCUUCCUUCCUUCGUCCUCCUCUCCCCUCCCCUCUCCUCCUCUCCCUCCUUCCUGCUCUAUUGCCCAGGCUGGAGUGCAGUAGCGUGAUCAUAGCUCACUGCAGCCUCAUACUCCACAAGUGUAUCCUCCCGCCUUAGUCUCCUGAGUCACUGGGACUACAGACACACACCACCAUGCCUGGCUAAUUUUUUUAUUUUUUGGUAAAGACAGGGUCUCACUGUGUUGUCCAGGCUGGUCUCAAACUCCUGGGCUGAAAUGAUUCUCUUGCCUCAGCCUCUGAAAGUGCUGGGAUUAUAGGCGUGAGCUGCUGAACCCAGCCCUCCUAAUUUCUGAUUGAUUUUUGAGUAAGAUGAGUUUUAGUGCUAAAACAUCCCACGUCGGUAGCUCUUAGAGAAGUACUUAGUGAAAGAAACCACAUGCCUUCAAAUGCUCAUAUAUAUGUAUGUAAAGCAUACAUUGGUAUGUGGUUUUGGUUCAUUUUCUUCCACUUGUUUCUUUCUCCUGUUUUCUGAUUCUCCCCUAUAAUCCAUCCCUCCCUCCCUCCCUCCCUCCAUUUGUGCUGCUCACAAACUCAAGGGGCAUCACUUACAUGGGAUAAUUUGCCUUUACAGCCACCCACGGCUGCUUUGAGAAAGGAAGUGUUCCCAUCACCUGUUUUCCUUUGCUUGGCUGUACCUGUAAUGACUGAGCCCCACUGGGUGCGCAGGGCAAGACCAGCCUUCGUGUCUCUUGGCCCAAUGGAGGCCCCAGGAGGGGAACGUGUGGUUUGGAGAAGCCGCUUCUUGCACCACUGCUCCUGUAACUGACCUUGGGCUGUGUGGUCUGUCCAGCCUCGGUUCCCUGUCUUUAAGAUGCAUGUAACAGGACCUCUCGGAUUUCUUGGGAGGCAUUGGGUGGAAUAUAGCAGGUAGAUUUUGUAGGAUAGUAGGUGCUAAGUUCAGGUCAGUUACUUCCCCUUAAAUAGAGAAGACUCUAAGUGACAUUUGGAUAAUCUCCUGAGAGCACACUGUAACUUCUAUUGGAGGUCAUUGCCUUGACCUCCUUAUGCCCAGGGGCAGCUGAGUGCCCACUUGCCAAGGUGUGAGCAAUGCGCCCUGUUCUGCUGUGAGCCUUCUUGGGACCCUGCAUAGAGCCUGUUCCCUUCCACUCACUGCUGGCUGGUGUCUGUGGAACAGCCUUCCCUGGCCUUUUGGCGGCCCUGUCAGGGUCUGGAAAUCUGGCUUUGUCUCAGAAAUCUGGCUGCGGAAGAUUUUCCUUUGUGUACUGUCAUAAAUGCCUUAAAUGUAUUAGGGUGCUUUGCAAAUCUUUCUCUAAUCCGUUUUGACAAAUAGCUGAGUAGUAUUGGUUUUAUGUGAACUUGGCAAAAUUUGCUCCCGUUCAGGGUGACUGGGGCAUGUGACAAUUAGUGGGAGGUGGCAGGAUUCUUGAGUGUAGCAUUUCUCUGACUCAGCCGACUAUUUCCUUUUUCCUGUUGCUUUAUUAUUUAUUGUUGCUAUUCUUUCUGCCACCCUCUCCCUCCCUCCUUACAGAUGUCUGUCUUUCCAGGACUGUCCUUGUAUUUUUUUAUCUUCUCUCGCAUAGACAUCUAUGGCAGGUCCAUCCUUGAAUACCCACUGUUCCUUCCGGUGACUACCAUGGUGUGGCAGCUCUAAGGGCAGGGAGCUCAUCUCUGCUGAAUGCAGCCCAUUUUGUGGAUGCCAUGGCACCUAGAAACCAACUGGAUGCAGUUGAAUGUGCCUCCCUAUGGCCUCCCUGGGCUGGGAUUCAGAGCAGGGCUCACUUUUCUUCCAUUUGUUGGGACUAAUGUGUCUGAAGACACUGCCGGUGCCCCACCUGGUUCCCUCUUUUCCAGGUCAGGCAGCCCAGCUUGCUUUCCCCAUCCCUCCUCUAAUGCGUUCACAGCCCCCUCAUUCCUCUCCUAGGUGAUGGUGCUGUGGGCUUUCAGAGCUCAGCUACGAUGGACUGUGUCUUAGCACAACAGGCGUGAGGAACUGAUGAGGGCAUUGGGAACGGUGAGGUGCUGGGGCACAUUAGUCCUGGCUCCAGGGAAUAGCAGAACUCUGCCCCUAACAUUCCAUUUACUGGUGGAAAAAUAGACCAGCGGGUUCUUGCUGUUCUACUUGCUAGAUGAUAGAUUUUCUUCAUCUUGUUUACAAGAAAGAAUGUGGUUUCUUAGCCAAGGACUUGAUUUCUGGUUCCUGGUGAACAGUUUUCAGAGCACUCUGAGCCUCUUCAUUUGUAGAAAGGGAACUUUGAGAAAAUGCCCAGCACAGUGCCUGCCUGGGACAGAGCGAUUUCAGCAAAUGUUUACAGAAAUCCCAGUUUAGUUCAAGUUGUGAGCUGAGAAUCCUUGCUGUUGGUUUUAGGUUUCCAGCCUCAGGCCUUCAGAACCUUUGGGGGUUGUAUCCCUAACCUCAGCCGUACCCUAGAGGCCAGGUCAGCAGAGUGAGUGAUAAGCGCACUCGUUCCAUCAACCGUGCGGUUAGAAACGUAGAGGUUGUCAUUAGAAAGUGCAGUCUUUCUAUCCUACUUUUGAAUUUCAGGGAGGAGCUUCAGGAUUUGUAAAGACUUCAUCUAUAUUGAAGACUGCCCAAGAGUUAUGGCUUACCCGGCUGCAGGCAGCAUGCCACCUGUAUGCAGUACCUGUGCUGUGUCUAAGGAGGAAGGGCGACUUGGUGGUGGGGGCGGGGGAGAGGCAGGACUGCGAGUGCCACCAGAGCUUGAGAGAGCAAAGAGGAACAGAGGAGAUGGGGGUGGAGCUGUGCAGAGCAGGGCACAUGUGCGGCUCUGUGUGUAGAAAAUGAGUCCCGUGUGGCUCUGUGUGUGGAAACUGAGUCCCGUGGGGCUCUGUGCGUGGGGGCUGAGUCCCGUGUGGCUCUGUGCAUGGAAACUGAGUCCCGUGCGGCUCUGUGCGUGGAAACUGAGUCCCGUGUGGCUCUGUGUGUGGAAACUGAGUCCCGUGCAGCUCUGUGCGUGGAAACUGAGUCCCGUGCGGCUCUGUGCGUGGGGGCUGAGUCCCGUGUGGCCCUGUGCAUGGAAACUGAGUCCCGUGUGGCUCUGUGUGCCUGGGGGAUGAGUCCUGUGUGGCUCUGUGUGUGUGGAAACUGAGUCCCGUGUGGCCCUGUGCGUGGAAACUGAGUCCCGUGUGGCUCUGUGUGUGUGGAAACUGAGUCCCGUGCGGCUCUGUGCGUGGGGGCUGAGUCCCGUGCGGCCCUGUGCGUGGAAACUGAGUCCCGUGUGGCUCUGUGCGUGGGGGCUGAGUCCCGUGUGGCCCUGUGCGUGGAAACUGAGUCCCGUGCGGCUCUGUGCGUGGGGGCUGAGUCCCGUGCGGCCCUGUGCGUGGAAACUGAGUCCCGUGCGGCCCUGUGCGUGGAAACUGAGUCCCGUGCGGCUCUGUGCGUGGAAACUGAGUCCCGUGCGGCUCCGUGCGUUGGGGCUGAGUCCCGUGCGGCCCUGUGCGUGGAAACUGAGUCCCGUGCGGCUCCGUGCGUUGGGGCUGAGUCCCGUGCGGCCCUGUGCGUGGAAACUGAGUCCCGUGCGGCCCUGUGUGUGGAAACUGAGUCCCGUGCGGCUCCGUGCGUUGGGGCUGAGUCCCGUGCGGCCCUGUGCGUGGGGGCUGAGUCCCGUGCGGCUCUGUGCGUGGAAACUGAGUCCCGUGCGGCUCCGUGCGUUGGGGCUGAGUCCCGUGCGGCUCCGUGCGUUGGGGCUGAGUCCCGUGCGGCCCUGUGCGUGGGGGCUGAGUCCCGUGCGGCCCUGUGCGUGGGGGCUGAGUCCCGUGCGGCCCUGUGCGUGGGGGCUGAGUCCCGUGCGGCUCUGUUUGUGGGGGUUGAGUCCCGUGCGGCUCCGUGCGUGGGGGCUGAGUCCCGUGCGGCUCUGUGUGCGUGGGGGCCGAGUCCCGUGCGGCUCUGUGUGCGUGGGGGCCGAGUCCCACGCUGCUCUGUUUGCGUGGAAACUGAGUCCUGUGCGGCUCUGUGCGUGGGGGCUGAGUCCCGUGUGGCUCUGUGUGCGUGGGGGCUGAGUCCCUUGUGGCUCCGUGCGUGGAAACUGAGUCCCGUGUGGCUCUGUGCGUGGGGGCUGAGUCCCGUGCGGCUCUGCGUGGAAACCGAAUCCCAUGCGGCUCUGUGUGUGGGGGCUGAGGCUGAGUCCCAUGCGGCUCUGUGUGUGGAAACUGAGUCCCCUGUGGCUCUGUGUGUGGAGACUGCAUCCUGUGCGACUCUAUGUGUGGGGCUGAGUCCUGUGUGCCAGUCUUCCCAUUGCCAUCUCAGGGAUCCUCAGGGCAGCCUGGUGAGGACAGUGAGGGCACGGGAUUGCAGCUAACACACAGAGCUGUGCAGUGAGGCAGGCAGGAGCUUGCUUGGGAGAGAGGCAGGGGAGUCGAGGGGCACCUGGCACCUUAUCUGGGCCAGCUGGCCUGGGUUCGAGUCCCAGCUCUGCCCAUUGGCAGCCAUGUGACCUUGGAUGCUUCACUCAACCCUCCUGUGCCCGAAUUUCUCCAUCGAUAAAAGGAAGAUGUUGGUAAUCGUAUUACCCACCUCAUGGGUUCUUAUAAAGAUGGAAAGAAUAAGAAUCAAUCAUGUUCCGAGCUUGAGACACAGCUGGCUGAUUUUAAGUGUAUGUUAUGGUUAAAGUGAGGGAGUCGAGCUUGGACUGUGGACCACCUGACUGCAUUGCUGUCCCUCUAAAGGUCAUGAUUGGGUGGUAACUGAACUUCAGCUUCUCCUGGAUUCAUAAUCUUAUUUCAUUUCAUAAAGUACAAUCAUACAGUCAACAUGACUUUAGAAUAUUGGAGGAAACUUUCUAUGUUCCUCAAGUACCAUUUAAUUAAAGAAAAAAAAAAGAAUUUUGGAUGAAACUAAUAUAACCCUGGGGUGGGCAAGUCUGUUGGGGGCAUGGGAGGGGCUAUGAUGGAGCAGGGCAGGACACGACCCGGCCCUGUCCCCUCUGGUGGAUUGGGCCCCACCUGUCCCUUUCCAGGCCCAGAGUUGAGCAGUUGGUUGAGUGGGUGGGUGGGUACCGUUUGAAAGAGCGAGUGGGGGCUGGUUGCGGGAUGGACCUGAGUGGCUAGGAUGGGUCCUUUGAGGAGGUGGCCCUGCCAGGCGGCUGCUUUACGUCAACGGCCAGUGAAGCUGGGGCUGCAGACCUGGAGGGCUUCCCAGCCCCGCCCCCGAGUUAUCCUCAGAGCAGGCCUUGCUGCUCUUUCCAAAGGGUGUCUGCAGACCGUUAGACAGUUGCUUGGCCAAUGUUCAACAGUGUGCAGGAAAAUGCUUAGAAAGCCAGGAACGAAUGGUUUCUGAAGUAUUCACCAUCAUUCAAUUCCACAGUGUCCCUUUAUGAGUUUAGCUAAUGGGGAGUUGACUUCUCUGUGUAGAUAUUCUGAGCCCGAUUGCUUAGGUGAUGGCAUUCUUGGCAGGGAAGCCGCUAGCCUGUUUUUCGGAGUAGAUGUUGUCCUGUGCUUCCUUCCCAUGUGGGACUGCCAUGCAGGUUGAAGACGGUUUUGUGCUUUUCUCUGCAAAUGGCUGUUCUUUGGACUGUGUGAGGUGAUUCUGCGUAGCCUCUCCCUUCUUCCAGGAUUCUGAAUCUGGAUUGAUUUUGUUGAUGAAGCUUUCUGAGAUGCAUUGCUGAAAAGAGUAGUUGAAGAAUGUGUCUGGAGAAAGCAUAUGGGUGCAUUUCACAACUGUGCUGUUUCAUAAAAGCGUUUCAAGUACAGUCUUCCCGAACCUGGAGGAUUCGCAACUGGCCUAUAAACAGACUCCAGUAUUUCAAGGUUGAGGAAGACGUUGGCAAAUUGAUCUGUAAAAUUAUAUAAGAGCUCUCUCUUUUCUUUUACCUGAGUUAAAGCUGAGUUGCCCAAGCCAGAACCUGGUGCUGUUCUGACCCCCUCCUGGCUCCCUGAUCCAUCCACUGUGUCGCCAAGGCCUGUGAUUCUACCUUCUAAGUGUUUUCCACAUGGCUCCUUUCCUCCCGCUGUGGUCACUGCCUUCAAUUCUCAACAUUUCUUGCCUGGACUUUUGCAACAGCCUCUGAACAGACUGCCCUGCCUCCAGCCUCUGCCGUCUCUCCCCUCCUCAUAUCCUUCCCUGCGCCUUCCAAACUCCUGGUCUAGGACCUCGUUCUGAGAACCGCCUUACCACCUAGUGGCAGGGCUGACCUGUCACUGCGUAGCUUUGAAGGUCAACGCCAAACUUACCUGUGUGGCCUGGACGGGGUCUCUGUCUCCAGCCCCCAUUUCACUCAGUUCCUCCGGGGACACUCGAAGCCCUCCCCCUUCCCACUGUGCUGCCUGGAGCAUGGCUUUCUCUGUCCUGCAGCACAAAUGUCAGCUGCCCAGGUGAGCCCUUUUCUGGGCUCAUCGCAAUUUGUCAAAACGUGUGACAGGGAUGAAUAGCUCCAUGCACCCAGGAGCAAGGCGUGCCACAUCUCUUCAUUUUUCUUGAGAAAUAAAUCUCCUUUGAUCCCUGACUCACUGAGAAAGAUGGGGUGGCUGAUAUCAGUCAUCUGGGGACUGUCCUCCCCAGGCACGUUUCCGAGGACUUGUCACUCAGUCACACCUGGCCCCACUCCCCAGGGCUUCGUUGGCCAUGGGUCCUGCUUGCCUGGUGCUGAGAUCUUCUUCAAGGUCUGCUGAAGUCAUCUCCUGUUGGGGUGGCCCUGGGACUCCACUCUGCUGCACACAGCUCAGGCCUCCAGGGGUCUUCCUCAGCCCCCUCCUCACUACUCCUGAGGUCUUUGCCCUCCCCUGGGUGGGUCCCUCUUCUCCUCCCACCCCUGAGCACUCAGCCUCCUCCUCACCCCCACGUGGAUCUGCUCGAUCUAGGUUUAGAGCUCUGGUUUUAAGCAUCGAUAUGUUUAAGCAUUAUCUGGGGAGCUUGUUAAAAAUACGGAUUCCUGGACUCCACCCCAAGAGAUUCUGACUCAGAAGCUUAGAUGAUGCCUGGCAGUGAACGUGUGUUUUAGCAAGAAUGGCGGGCUCCUUGACACGGUUGUUCUGUAGUUUGGACAGUGAGUAGCACUCGCCCAGACCUUAAAAACAAAGGCUUUUUCGGGGCUUGUUUUUAGGGCUCCCCCGACUUCUUCCUGUGGACCCAGGAACACAGAAGAUCAUUUUGCUACAGAGUCCGCAUAAGCCCUCUGCCCUCCAGCCCUGCAUUCACAGCUAGCCUGGGAGCUCCUCGAGGGCAGGGCGUGGCUUCAUUCCUCCUGCACAACUCCUGGUACCUCGCACUGGGUCCGUGGCCAGAUGUGGGCAGGAGCAGUCUCGGGGACAACAGACACAGCCCGCUGAGGAAGGCACCCAACCCUGGGCUUGGCUUUCCUUUCCUUUCUGGCAUGGGGCUCAGGUGUCCAGAGGCGGGAGGAUUCCGAGGGUCUCUGGUGGCUGCCUUCUCCAGAUUUGGGCUUGGACUGGGCACAGCUGGGAAUCAGUUAUGUUUUGUUUUGUUUUGAAUUGGCAUAGUGACCGUCUUAGGCAGAAGGCAGGCUGCCGCAGGGCCUCCACGCUCAGGCGCUGCCUGGCGAUGGCUUCUCCGUGGAGGAGAGGGAACUGCUCUGAAGCAAGCCCAGCACCGCAGUCCUGGCCAGACCCGUGGGCAGAUCCCUGGAGUCCUGUCCCCACACUACCCUUGGAGCUGCCUUCCGAGUCGGUUCAAGCUCUACGUUCGUGACAUCAAACCUCCUGUUGGGCCAUUUCCGAGAACUCCCAUCAGUUUCUGUAUAGUGUAAAAGUUUCAGAGGCGGAGCACAGAGAGCUGCGGCUGGGACAAGGAGCACCCGCGUGCAGGUGCGACCCUGCAGGAUGCUGGCAGCGGCGUGGCCAGGGGCGCCCGUGUUCUGAGGGCCUGAGGGCCAGCCCCUCCACCCGCGCCAUGGCCUCCGCGCCCUGGCUGGACGGCUGACGGGAGCAGGGACCGCCGCCGCCCAGGUGCCACACCCAGGUACCGCCCGCCCGCGCGAGAGCCGGGCAGGUGGGCCGCGGAUGCUCCCAGAGGCCGGCCCAGCAGAGCGAUGGACUUGGACAGGCUAAGAUGGAAGUGACCUGAGCCUCGCCCGGCGGCUUCCUCGACGGGACAGCGCAAGAGUUGGAGCACAGGCUUGUCCGGGGAGCAGUAUGCCGGAAGCUGGUUUUCAGGCCACAAAUGCUUUCACAGAGUGCAAAUUCACCUGCACCAGUGGUAAAUGCUUGUAUCUUGGUUCGCUGGUCUGUAACCAACAGAACGACUGUGGGGACAACAGUGACGAAGAGAACUGUCUCCUGGUGACCGAGCACCCGCCUCCGGGCAUCUUCAACUCGGAGCUGGAGUUCGCCCAAAUCAUCAUCAUCGUCGUGGUGGUCACGGUGAUGGUGGUGGUCAUCGUCUGCCUGCUGAACCACUACAAAGUCUCCACGCGGUCCUUCAUCAACCGCCCGAACCAGAGCCGGAGGCGGGAGGACGGGCUGCCGCAGGAAGGGUGCCUGUGGCCUUCAGACAGCGCCGCACCGCGGCUGGGCGCCUCGGAGAUCAUGCAUGCCCCGCGGUCCAGGGACAGGUUCACAGCGCCGUCCUUCAUCCAGAGGGAUCGCUUCAGCCGCUUCCAGCCCACCUACCCCUAUGUGCAGCACGAGAUUGAUCUUCCUCCCACCAUCUCCCUGUCCGACGGUGAAGAGCCACCUCCUUACCAGGGGCCCUGCACCCUGCAGCUCCGGGACCCUGAACAGCAGAUGGAACUCAACCGAGAGUCCGUGAGGGCCCCACCCAACCGAACCAUAUUUGACAGUGAUUUAAUAGACAUUGCUAUGUAUAGCGGGGGUCCAUGCCCACCCAGCAGCAACUCGGGCAUCAGUGCAAGCACCUGCAGCAGUAACGGGAGGAUGGAGGGGCCACCCCCCACAUACAGCGAGGUGAUGGGCCACCACCCAGGCGCCUCUUUCCUCCAUCACCAGCGCAGCAACGCACACAGGGGCAGCAGACUGCAGUUUCAGCAGAACAAUGCAGAGAGCACAAUAGUACCCAUCAAAGGCAAAGAUAGGAAGCCUGGGAACCUGGUCUGAUUCCUUCCAACGUGCACUUCAGCUGGAGAAAGAAACCAAGAAGGGAAGCGGCCGCUGGGCCCCUCCUGCGCACAGUGUUGUUCAGUUUCACAUGGUACAAAUAAGUAAAACCAAAUGAGCAAACACGGUCUUUGUUUCUGAUUCCUUUUAGGGGAAUUGCAUGCAAACUAGACUGAAAUGAUACAAACUUCCAUCUGGUCUGACCGCAAACAGUGUUUAUUUGGGGACAGGGGUUGGGAUGGGGGUGUGGGCAGGGGAAAACAGAGAACGGGAUGCUUUGAAGAUACCAUGAAAUAAAACCCACAGAGGUAUUUGAUGUAUUUAAUUGUGAAAGGAGACUUUGCAGAUAAAUGAGGCCAGAAUGGCAUGUUUUAUAAUUAACUGAAUAAAGAAGGAAGCAUUAUUAUAUAUUAUUGUGGGGAAGAACCAGCCAGUUCGCUUUUUCUCCUAAGGUGUGGAACUUUUAUUUUGUUUUAAAAAUAUGAAUCAAAAUUCCUGUGUUGUGUGCCAAGGUAUAAAGUGGAGAAGUUAGAUGAGUGCAAGGAGCUCCUUUGUGUUGUGAUGAUGUGUUUUAAAAGUUGCACUAUCUUAAUGUUGAAAAUAUUUACAAGGGAACUGUUUUACGUGAAGUUCUGUAUGUUGUCUUUUCACCUGUGGAUUGUAAUCAGGCCCAAGGAAUAUCCUGGAGUGGUCCCCAGAAGCAUCCAAGAAAAGAUAUUUGGGGACGUAGCCUAACAUUUUACCAACUUACGUAAAUCAAAAAAGUCAUUAUUGUUGCAGGAGUUUGCAUCAAAUAGCAGUGCAUCGCUGAAGCUUUUGGAGACUUUUGGAUGGAAGAUAAGAUAGGGAAGAUUAAGUUCCAGCAUUUCUGACUUGUUAUUUUGAGUUACUCUGCUACUCUUAGGCUGCAUAGUUUAUGAGAAAAUGAACACAUGCAUUUAUGGAUCCAGUAUCAUGCAGUGCUGCCCUCAUCCUCCAGCAGUGCAAUUUCUUCAGUAAUUUAGAUUUUUUUCACUAUAGCAUGAAAUAUAUUCAAAUACAUACCUUAUUUUAUGCAAUAAAUUGUUUAAAAUGCAAGGUGGUUAUUCUGCAUACUGUUGAAAUAUGUGACUCCUCAGUAUAUUCCCAUUGCCUCUCCCCCUUUCCUCGACAGCUUAGUUCAGUUCUGCAGGGCUGCUCAGUUCACAGGAGGCUCCCAGCAGCCACCCCACAUCCAGCCUACACAGAACUUCGUGUGGGAGUGGUGUGGGUGGUGGUUUCUUAUGCUUUGGAAGCCCCUAGAAAUAAUGACGGAAGAAUGCCAUGUUGCUGAUCGUGGUAAUAAGCCAUUGUGGGUUAUUGUAUGUCACUAGUAUUAGCAUAGCAUUCUUAAAGGAAUGCAGUGCUCAAAACCUACCCAAAUUCCCGCAGGAUUCUACCAAACCCUUCCCCAGGCCAGCUUUUGUACUGAAGGCAAGAACUGGACAGUCAGAGAACAGUGGAGGGGGCAAGUGACUGAAGAGCACCGGGUAAAAAGCACAACAUGCAGUUAAAAUGCAACUAGAAAACUAAUUUUAAAUAUUGUUAGUUUUAAUAUUCCUGAUAUUUACAAAUAUUCAUUCUUAUAUACAAUGAAAAAAAUAACUUUCUUCUGCAGAUGUAAGCACUGGCUUUUAUAAGAGCAGCAGCCAACACGUUUAGCAGACACUGCGCGUGGAGAAGGGCUUAUCUGCAGUACACUCUGCCAUGUGGAGGGUGGGCCUCUGUGGCCUCUUCACAUAACAAGAUGAGCUGGAAUGAUGAUUCCAUGACUCCCACCUAUGCAGCCUUAAAGCCAAAUCCGCGUGUGUGUGUUUGUGUCUGUCUGUGGGUCUCGAAGGUGAUCCGUCGGUGCGGUGGCUCUGUGCUGUAACUGGAGAGACUGUUCCAAACCCCAAGAGUUGUCUGAUCCUAGUCUGUUCCCUUCUGCUUCUUACCUCUGUAGAUAGGUCACUGGUUUUUGUUUGUUUGUUUUGAGGAUUGGAAUUUCCAUUACAUUCAUCCUUUGCACACAGUAACAUCCACAGAACUAGUCCAACUCUUAAAAGGAGAGAGGAAAAACACAGGCACCAGUUGUCAGCUCAUGCUUACAACCUGUGUGGAAGUAUAUACAGUUGAGAGUCACAGUGGAGGUUCUGAGACUGGAUUCAGUCUUGUUCCAGUGACAGUUGGAAGGCCUCUGCUGGAGAGACACCAGCUCUCAGGGCAGAGAUUGGCUUGGGGCCAGAAGGACCCUCCCCAACCCUGGAGACACCCUGAAGGUUCACUGGCUCUCCAGAUUAGCCUCUCUUCCUCUGUCAGGCAAAGAUGAGGAGCCCGUGUUCCCAUCGGGCCCUGCUGGCAGGGACUUGCAGUGGAUUCUUGGUCAGGUGUGCCCACAGAUGCGGAGGCGAGGUGAGUGAUUCCAUCAUUUCAGUUCUCACCUGCAGUUUUGGUGAAGCAGGAGAUGCACCCCACAGCUCUAGCUCUCAAAUGGCUUCACAGUCCUUACUUCUCUACCUGCCUCAAGAAGGGGCUCAGAGCAGAGACUUGUGAAUUCCUUAGUAACUGUGAGUAUAUGAAUGUGUUGCACAUGUCCACAGUAUUGGCGAGAUAAUUACAUAAUUCAGAUACCUUUAAUCAUCUUUCAAGAAAGAGGCUCCUCCCAUUCAACCACCCUAGAGAACUGCCUUUGUUAAAUAGUUAUUUAAAGACUCAUACAUAUCAAACCAUGACUUUGAAAGGUCUUCGAGGCUGGGGCUCUGUAAUGAAUUAGUUUAAAAGCCAAGGUCAUAACAUGAAUUGAUGGUCAAUUUCCCUUCAGCAGAAGGAAAAGGUGAUUUAGAUCAGUAGCUCUUUUGAAGGUUGUGGCUGACCUGUUCAUACCGUGUCGCCUCAUGGCUAGUGUGGCGUUGAAAGAGUAGCGACUGGGAAGAUACAACUUACACAGUGGGGCCUAUUGUUCUUUCAAGAACCCUUUUUUUAGCUUAUAGAACCCAUGGGUCCAGUUUAGUAACGAGUGAUUUAGGCAAUCAAUGAUAGGUUUAUAAUCUUAGAUUAUUCCAGCAAAGUGUGGAUUGCAUUGUUAGGAAGAACAUUUGGUGGGAAUGAACACUCCUGGGCAUACCGCUGACUUUUGUCCCUUGUUCCCGGUGUAGGAGACCCAAGGCAUCUUGAAUCCCAUCUAUAAGAACACAAUCUUCCAGCAUACGUUUGCUUUUUCAGAAACUCUAGCAUUCUCUUUAAAUACUGACGCAAUCCUUAAUGGAAAAGAGAUUUCAUGAAGCAAAUUAUGUAUUUCAAUAGUUCUUCUAUUUUUAGUGUCCAAAAUUUACUAAUACAGAAGCUUGACAAGCAUGUCCUCACCCUCCCCACCACAUAAACACAUGGACACACACCCAAGCCACAAGAAAUCCCAAGAGAGCAGAAGCGAAUUUUUAAAAGAUUUAUCGUGAGGACUGCAUUUCCAUUCACUAAUUUUGGCUCAAACUUAUGAGGCAGGAAAUAGGGGCCAACAGUAAAUGGGGGAGGCCUCCUGACACCAGCAGAGGAAUUUUGUACCCAGGCGAGGACUUCUUGAACUUCUGCGUAUCUCCGUUUGAUCUCUUUCACCUUUAUUUCAUCUUCAUAAGAAUGAGAAAGGCUCAAAAGGAAGCACUUUUAGAAAUCUUCUCUGACCUAGAAGAAUCCAUCCAAAUCCCUGCCUUCCUCUCUGAACCAACAGUUCCCUUCUCUGACAGGGGCCAUCCUCUAUCUUCCAUCCAGCGGCUCUUCUUUUUAGGAAGGCUCUGGUGCAGAGCACUUCAAAUAUGUCCUCAGGCCAGAUACUGAUUGCUAGUAGAGAGACACCCGGCACCCAGUCCGAAGCCCUCCCUCAAAGGACCGGCUCAUGGCGUUGGUCACUGGCAGGCUCAGAGACAUUCUGCUGUGGGCGCAGGGAGCCCGGCCCCCCAUGCAGCCAUGACUGGAUGCGCCCCCAUCUCGGGGGCUUGCUGCACUGCUUGUUUAUUGAAUUUUGCUACUUAGAAUGGCAACAUUAACUUUGUGUACCAUUCAUUUUUUAAAAAUUUUCCAAAGCUCGGCAGUGUAUGAAAGAAAAAACUGGGAAAGAUACUUGGUUUCUGUUAACUUUUGUGUUGCUUGCUUAAGUGAUUAAAGCCAGUGCUUGGAGCCAAGCCUUCAUGCCACGAACAUGCUCCACAGCCUGCCCUUUGCUCUCCUGCUCACACUGACCAAGAAUGCCGCGUGCUUGGCCUACUGAGGUGAAAGGACAAUUGAAUGACAGGUGGGCAAAGGGAGAACUUCCCCUUCUUGGUGCGAGGAAAGUCACAAAUUUAAAAAUGUUGCUUCCAGCCCAGAUCCUAAAUGCUAGUUCUCAGCAGCUGCGUGGCUUACCGUUCGCCAUUUCCACCACCGCCAGCUGCCAGCACCGCUACAGAUCACAGAGAUGUGAACAGACAAUGGAAAGCACUCUUAGCCUUGCAGUGGUCUACAUUUUUUAGGAACCAAUAUUUCAGCAUUCUUUAUUACCCGGCACGCUGUGUCCUUUGCAGAGUUCAAGUUUAUGUUACUGCCAGGGUCAGACAGUCAUUUGCUGCUGCUGCUGCUGCUGCUGCUUCUCGAACUGGAUGCAUUAGGAAGCUGCUGUCUGAGUGUAGGAAUGUCUUGCUAAGAAAGCAAUGUCUUCCUUCAUCCUUUUCUUUCUUCCCUCUGCGUGUCCUUGUUUUUGUGUAAUGCGGGAGAGGGUUAGAGCUAUAGAGAUUAUAUAUACACUAUCCGUGCACAUUAUAUAUAUGUAGAUAUACCCCUAUCAUGUCAGAGAUCUGCAUGUCAGUUUUUCAGCAACUAAGGUGCCUCAUGUUCUGAGUUCAGCAGAUAUAGGAACCAAGCCGCCCCCUCCUGCACUUGAUGCUCCCACCUUUGUUGUGCCUCACUUAAAAUGGUGCUUUUUUCAGUUGUCUGUCUUUUCUUAUGUUUUUAUUUGUAAGGUGCUGUAUAUAAGUUGAAUAUAUUAUGCACAUAUCCUACCCAAUGGGUAGAACAAAAAGUUGUUAAUACUGUAAUAUAAUGUAUAGAUGAUACCAAUUUUAACAGAAAUGGCAUAGAAUUUGUGAAUGCCUAUGUGCUUUGUCCUCUUUUGUAAGGAAAUUUGCAAAUGGAUGCAUACAGAUUAAAGUCUAUGUAGUUUAUUUUCCUAUUAAAUAUCAAUAUUAUAACACAAGAGAAAGAAGUGUGAACAAACAAGCAACAGUUUAUGACCAGCGUAUAUAUAGCAAUGGAAAGUUGCAUCUUUGCUGUGAAAACACUUUAAAGAAAAUACUUUUUAAAAAAUCCCACAGCUUUUUGGUUGCCACUAGACGCUUCUUAUUUUAAUCAUUUUAGUAAUGCUCAGCUGGACCAGUGUUAGUUAUAUUUGAGUCAGAAAAAUGUUGUUUUUCAACUUGCUUUAUAAUCUCCUGCAUCUAUCUCCUGCUGUAGCAUCACGAAGGUGUCAGGCAACAGUGAAAAGUGCACAUUUUUGUUGUUGCAGAAACUGUGUCAGAGGAAUAAGUAAAUCAGCCUGCAGCAGAAGACUUUGUUCAGCUCCAGAGGCAUCUGUGACCGUCUGUGUCCAAGUCUCUCUGUGCCUUUUUCUUUUACAAACUGAAGCUGUGGAGCCAAUGAAGUAACAGUAGAGAUUGUAGGGAAAGAAUACCUCAGGAAAAACAAAUACACUUACAAGAAGACCCUGUUCUUAGAAAAUGUGUUUAGUUAUGGGUUAGCACUAGAAGAGACUUGGCUGUCAGCCAGCCAAGUGAAGGACCUCUCAUCCAUUCCCAUUCAUGUCCCAUCAUAAUACGGACCCAAAAAGCAAACUCGGUUUUGCCAUCAGUUAGAAAUUACGUUUUGGAUUGUAUAUUGUUACAUCUCUCUUCCGGCUUAGUUUUUAGUGUCUGAUUGUGACCUCUGCAUUUAUCUUCAAAUACCCUAAUUUUAAAACAAAAGAACAAGAAAAGUUUAUAACACCAUGUUCACUAAAACCACGGUUGAAUCUUGGGUGUGGGCAUCCUUUCGAGUGUUGUCCAUAAGAGCAGUUCGUGGAAUUUUGCCCAUCUGACCCAUAUUAUCAGCUUAUUCUGCCACCAGAGUAGAGUCUAAUAAAUUCCAAAGUUUUUAUUUGCUCCAUGGUGUAUGUUCUGACUUUGAAAAUGUCAGAUUCUAUAAUCAUACCCCUAACAUCCAGGAAACAAAUGACAGAUUAUCUUUAAACUGAAAUUGACUCUACAAUGCAACCCUUAAUGCUGAAUGGAUUAAAAAAGUCAGCCCUUUUAGUAUCUGUUUGAAAGGGCCGUAAAAAGUUGACACUUUUGUUGUUGUGGAUCCUGCGUGUCUAGACCCACGUGUUGUUUCCAUCGUAUACUGUAGGGUGCACCCCUUGGGAUUCAUCAUUAAGAACUGAGGCUCACUGUUGUCAGAAACAAAGCUCCCACCCCCCAGGUUCAACCUUGUGGGAGAACUGUUGAGCAUGAGAAUGUUCUAGACUCAGAGGUACUAAAAUUUGUUACCACAUCAUUGCUUCCUUUCUACAGGACGAAUUGAGGCUUAAACUUUACUGUUAAUGAUACUGGUUCAUUUUAAUGUGCUUGUUGGUAUGUUGCUAUUUUUCAUUUCAUAGCUUUCAAAAAUCAUGCUAAUUGUAUACUUGUCUAGUUUAAGGCUAUUUUAAAAUAUGUACAAUACUAUUCACAGCAUUUAGUUCGUUUAAUUUUUAUUAUAAAGCAAUCUACUAAAAAAGUACAACUGUAUUUGAACUUUUCAAUAGUUGUUUGUGAGCUAUGAUAAUCAAAAGUCAUUAAAGUCUUUUUUAACAAACAUUCGUGCUUACUUUUCAACAUAAUUCCCAGUUAUAUACAGAAAAAGAUUUCCACCUGUCACGUAUCUGCCUCUUUUACCUGAGCAAUGGUGUAGUUCUUAGACCUAAGGUCUGUAAUUGCAAUACUUUUAAAGAAAGAUGUUGCUCUAAGUGCUGUUUGUUAGUUAUGAAAUCAGAUUUUUCUGCUUGUUCUUAAUGCUGUGGUCAAACCAUAGCACAAAAUCAUUAAAAAUAAUCAGCGGCAUAC